GCAUUUCCGGUAGCGGCGGCGGGAAAUCGGCUGUGGGAGAGAGGCUAGGCCUCUGAGGAGGCGAAUCCGGCGGGUAUCAGAGCCAUCAGAACCGCCACCAUGACGGUGGGCAAGAGCAGCAAGAUGCUGCAGCAUAUUGAUUACAGGAUGAGGUGCAUCCUGCAGGACGGCCGGAUCUUCAUUGGCACCUUCAAGGCUUUUGACAAGCACAUGAAUUUGAUCCUCUGUGACUGUGAUGAGUUCAGAAAGAUCAAGCCAAAGAACUCCAAACAAGCAGAAAGGGAAGAGAAGCGAGUCCUCGGUCUGGUGCUGCUGCGAGGGGAGAAUCUGGUCUCAAUGACAGUAGAGGGACCUCCUCCCAAAGAUACUGGUAUUGCUCGAGUUCCACUUGCUGGAGCUGCCGGGGGCCCAGGGAUCGGCAGGGCUGCUGGCAGAGGAAUCCCAGCUGGGGUUCCCAUGCCCCAGGCUCCUGCAGGACUUGCUGGGCCAGUCCGUGGGGUUGGCGGGCCAUCCCAACAGGUGAUGACCCCACAAGGAAGAGGUACUGUUGCAGCCGCUGCAGCUGCUGCCACAGCCAGUAUUGCCGGGGCUCCAACCCAGUACCCACCUGGCCGUGGGGGUCCUCCCCCACCUAUGGGCCGAGGAGCACCCCCUCCAGGCAUGAUGGGCCCACCUCCUGGUAUGAGACCUCCUAUGGGUCCCCCAAUGGGGAUCCCCCCUGGAAGAGGGACUCCAAUGGGCAUGCCCCCUCCGGGAAUGCGGCCUCCUCCCCCUGGGAUGCGAGGCCUUCUUUGACCCUUGGCCACAGAGUAUGGAAGUAGCUCCGCAGAGGCGUGGGCUCGAUUCCUCAGGGCCACGUUACCACAGACCUGUUUGUUUCUUAUGCUGUUGUUCGUGGAGUCUCAUGGGAUUGUCUGGUUUCCCUUACAGGGCCCCCUCCCCCGGGAAUGCGCCCACCAAGGCCCUAGACUCAUCUUGGCCCUCCUCAGCUCCCUGCCUGUUUCCCGUAAGGCUGUACAUAGUCCUUUUAUCUCCUUGUGGCCUAUGAAACUGGUUUAUAAUAAACUCUUAAGAGAACAUUA